CUCCCUCCCCAGCCUUCCCCGCGAGCGGACGCGGCAGCGCCUCUGUCUCGCUUUUUCUUAUUUUUCCCCCCUUUCCCCUUUCUUUUUUUUUUUUUCUUUUCUUUUCUCCCCUCCCCCCCUUUCACCAUUUCCCCUCGGAGGCGCUUUCCCCGGGCAGGGGCAGAGCCGGUCUCACCCCCCGCCUCUCCCCGGCCCCCGCCGCCCUAUGGCGAGAGGGAGCCCCCUCCCAACCCGGGCUCGAGCGGCGGCGGCCUCAGGCCGGGGGUCAUCAUGGAACUAAUUCGCUGACCGACCCAGCGGCCGCAGCCGUGCGUCCCGCUCGAGCGCCAGCGCCCGCGCCCGCGCCCCCCGAUCCGCUUCCCCUUUCUCCCUCCUCAGUUGGCCGAGUCGUCCCGCGCGCACCGCCUCCGCGCGCCUAUGAGAAUGAGGUGGUAACGGGCCCCCGGAUGACCCCGCGUCACCACUGUGAGGCCUACAGCUCUGCCGGGGAGGAGGAGGAGGAGGAAGAGGAGGAGAAGGUAGCUACAGCAAGCUGGGUAGCAGGCAGAUCCAAAGGAUAUCAUGAAGUUUCCAGGGCCUUUGGAAAACCAGAGAUUGUCUUUCCUGUUGGAAAAGGCAAUCACUAGGGAAGCACAGAUGUGGAAAGUGAAUGUGCGGAAAAUGCCUUCAAAUCAGAAUGUUUCUCCAUCCCAGAGAGAUGAAGUAAUUCAAUGGCUGGCCAAACUCAAGUACCAAUUCAACCUUUACCCAGAAACAUUUGCUCUGGCUAGCAGUCUUUUGGAUAGGUUUUUAGCUACCGUAAAGGCUCAUCCAAAAUACUUGAGUUGUAUUGCAAUCAGCUGUUUUUUCCUAGCUGCCAAGACUGUUGAGGAAGAUGAGAGAAUUCCAGUACUAAAGGUAUUGGCAAGAGACAGUUUCUGUGGAUGUUCCUCAUCUGAAAUUUUGAGAAUGGAGAGAAUUAUUCUGGAUAAGUUGAAUUGGGAUCUUCACACAGCCACACCAUUGGAUUUUCUUCAUAUUUUCCAUGCCAUUGCAGUGUCAACUAGGCCUCAGUUACUUUUCAGUUUGCCCAAAUUGAGCCCAUCUCAACAUUUGGCAGUCCUUACCAAGCAACUACUUCACUGUAUGGCCUGCAACCAACUUCUGCAAUUCAGAGGAUCCAUGCUUGCUCUGGCCAUGGUUAGUCUGGAAAUGGAGAAACUCAUUCCUGAUUGGCUUUCUCUUACAAUUGAACUGCUUCAGAAAGCACAGAUGGAUAGCUCCCAGUUGAUCCAUUGUCGGGAGCUUGUGGCACAUCACCUUUCUACUCUGCAGUCUUCCCUGCCUCUGAAUUCCGUUUAUGUCUACCGUCCCCUCAAGCACACCCUGGUGACCUGUGACAAAGGAGUGUUCAGAUUACAUCCCUCCUCUGUCCCAGGCCCAGACUUCUCCAAGGACAACAGCAAGCCAGAAGUGCCAGUCAGAGGUACAGCAGCCUUUUACCAUCAUCUCCCAGCUGCCAGUGGGUGCAAGCAGACCUCUACUAAACGCAAAGUAGAGGAAAUGGAAGUGGAUGACUUCUAUGAUGGAAUCAAACGGCUCUAUAAUGAAGAUAAUGUCUCAGAAAAUGUGGGUUCUGUGUGUGGCACUGAUUUAUCAAGACAAGAGGGACAUGCUUCCCCUUGUCCACCUUUGCAGCCUGUUUCUGUCAUGUAGUUUCAACAAGUGCUACCUUUGAGUGUAAACUAAGGUAGACUACUUUGGGAAUGAGAACAUGCAAAAUCAGGAAAGGCUGUAGAAGGAAAUAUACCUUAACAGGCUGAUUUGGAGUGAGCCAGAAAAAAAAAAUAAAACUCUCAUUAUUUGUGUGGCUAAUUAUAAUUCAGCGUUAUUUAAGCACAUAAAGACCAAAAAAAAAAAAAAGAAAUCCAAAAGAUCCAAACUUUUUUUAAACUUAAAAAAUCUCUUUGUAGUAUGUCAGUUGCACUUUUUUUCUGCCAUAAUGUAACGUAGCUUGCCCCGUCAAAAAUUCAAUUAAAAUUCAUGGCCAGCAAUCCUGUUCCCCCUCAGCAUCCUGAUUUAAUUUUCCUGUUGCUUUUGCUUGCUUCUCCAUUUAAUAGUUACUGAACUUUAUGCAUGUUGAUCUAUAUUGAUUUUCACUGCAGUUGAAUGAACAAAUUAUUUCAGUGUGACAGCCAUGACUCAAGUUCCAAUUAGUCUGAAAAGGGUACUUUGGAAUUGUCCCAUAUUAAUCAGAGAUGGCAAAAGAAAAAGUUCUCAUAUUACCAGGUUGAUUUUGUGUCUCAUUUCAAAUUUUAAUUUAAAAUUAUGGUUUUCAUUUUUGUUUACCUUAAAGUGAUGCUUAAAAGUGGCAUGUAAUUAGGACACUUAGGUUUGUUGAAAGCAUUUUCGACAUUUGUAUAAAAGAAUUUGUGAUAAAUAUAUCCAGGUGCUCACCAAAGAAACAUGUAUUAACAACUUAAAUUAGAUUUUUCUAACUGAUAGUUUUCACUCAUUUAUAAUCAGUAGGAGAGACUGUCUAGAUGUUGGGGCAGCUCUAUGAUUUAAGUCUGUAACAUGUUAUAACUGAAUUUAGUACCCUAGUUUUGUUAAGCUAUUAGGAUUUUCUAAUAGAACUUACUCCCCCUGCCUCCCCAGCCUUAUGUUUCUUUUAAUGACUUCUGGAUCCUGAGCUCCCUUUGCAGUCUGAAAAAGGUAUUGCAGUCAGAACUGUGUACUGAUGAUAAAAGCCUCUGGUAGCAAUAAAAAGUUGUCCUUAA